CAUGUCGCUCAUGGUCGUCAGCAUGGCGUGUGUUGGGUUCUUCUUGCUGCAGGGGGCCUGGACACAUGAGGGUGGUCAGGACAAGCCCUUCCUCUCUGCCUGGCCCAGCCCUGUGGUGUCUGAAGGAGAACAUGUGGCUCUUCAGUGUCGCUCUCGUCUUGGGUUUAACGAAUUCAGUCUGUCCAAAGAAGACGGGAUGCCUGUCCCUGAGCUCUACAACAGAGUAUUCCGAAACACCGUUUUCAUAGGCCCUGUGACCCCAGCACAUGCAGGGACCUACAGAUGUCGGGGUUCACACCCACACUUCCUCACUGGGUGGUCAGCACCCAGCAACCCCCUGGUGAUCAUGGUCACAGGAGUCCACAGAAAACCUUCCCUCCUGGCCCACCCAGGUCCCCUGGUGAAAUCAGAAGAGACAGUCAUCCUGCAAUGUUGGUCAGAUGUCAUGUUUGAGCACUUCCUUCUGCACAGAGAGGGGAAGUUUAAUGACACUUUGCGCCUCACUGGAGAGCUCCAUGAUGGGGUCUCCAAGGCCAACUUCUCCAUCGGUCGCAUGACGCAAGACCUUGCAGGGACCUACAGAUGCUACGGUUCUGUUCCUCAUUCCCCCUAUCAGUUGUCAGCUCCCAGUGACCCUCUGGACAUCGUGAUUACAGGUCUAUGUGGGAAACCUUCUCUCUCAGCCCAGCCGCGCCCCAUGGUUAAGGCAGGAGAGAGCGUGACCUUGUCCUGCAGCUCCCGGAGCUCCUAUGACAUCUACCAUCUAUCAAGGGAGGGGGAGGCUCAUGAACUUAGGUUCCCUGCAGUGCCCAAGGUCAAUGGAACCUUCCAGGCCAACUUUCCUCUGGGCCCUGCCACCCACGGAGGGACCUACAGAUGCUUCGGCUCUUUCCGUGACUCUCCCUACGAGUGGUCAGACCUUAGUGACCCACUGCUUGUUUCUGUCACAGAUUCUAUGAAGGAGAAAGGAAAAGAUGUGAUACUGUAAUUUUGCUCCAUUUGUCUAAAAUGAGUAGGCUGCAACUCCUCUUGAAGUGAUACCUUUUCUAGCUCUUGUUGGAGGUGUCUCAGGACUCAUUACUUCGGGGAACCUGCAACUGUGUCAGUCUGGGGAAACUGCAAAUAUUCUUGUCUUACAUUUGUCUCCAGCCAAUUGUGAUGGACUCCAGUGACCUGCAAUUGCUGUUAUUGCAGGUAAAAUGUACCUGAGUCAGGCCACAGUUCUCCUGGACUAUGAGCCCCUGGCCAUGUUCCUGAGGCAAUUCUGUUCAUCUAAAUAUAAUAAUAAUAACAC